GCAUUGAAGGGGCUGCUCCGAAUGGAGGGGGAGGGGAGGUGUUUAGGAGAAAGUAGGGGCUGUGGGUGUCGGGAGCCGGCUGACGGGUGGACAAGGGGGGGUUAGCAGCUGGGCUGCGACCGUUAGGGAGGGGCUCAAGGUGUGCAUGUGUGAGGGAAGAGAGAGAGAGAGAAGGGCGCCUCAGAGGUGACUUUCAGCCUGCGAGCCUUCUUCCCGGGGCGCCAUAAACGCCCCCAAUUUCCCAGCUGCUAAAGGAAGAGGAAGGUACCUGUGCGUGCACGCAGACGGGAAGGGCUGGGGAAGCGGGAGGACUGAGAAAAGCCGGAUCUUAGCAAAGCAAUGUCUCAAGAUGGUGCUUCUCAGUUCCAAGAAGUCAUUCGGCAAGAGCUAGAAUUAUCUGUGAAGAAGGAACUAGAAAAAAUACUCACCACAGCAUCAUCACAUGAAUUUGAGACACCGGGUUUUGCCAUAUUGCCGAGGCUGGUCUCAAACUCCUGAGCUCAAACGAUCAGCUGGCCUGAGCCUCCCAAAGUGCUGGGAUUACAGGCAUGCACCAACUACGCCCAGCCUGUAUUAGCUUUUAGGAUGUGAAAAAGUCUUGCUCCCUCCAUGUCCUAAUGGUCACACCAAAAAAGACCUGGAUGGAUUUCGGAAGCUAUUUCAUAGAUUUUUGCAAGAAAAGGGGCCUUCUGUGGAUUGGGGAAAAAUCCAGAGACCCCCUGAAGAUUCGAUUCAACCCUAUGAAAAGAUAAAGGCCAGGGGCUUGCCUGAUAAUAUAUCUUCCGUGUUGAACAAACUAGUGGUGGUGAAACUCAAUGGUGGUUUGGGAACCAGCAUGGGCUGCAAAGGCCCUAAAAGUCUGAUUGGUGUGAGGAAUGAGAAUACCUUUCUGGAUCUGACUGUUCAGCAAAUUGAACAUUUGAAUAAAACCUACAAUACAGAUGUUCCUCUUGUUUUAAUGAACUCUUUUAACACGGAUGAAGAUACCAAAAAAAUACUACAGAAGUACAAUCAUUGUCGUGUGAAAAUCUACACUUUCAAUCAAAGCAGGUACCCGAGGAUUAAUAAAGAAUCUUUACUUCCUGUAGCAAAGGACGUGUCUUACUCAGGGGAAAAUACAGAAGCUUGGUACCCUCCAGGUCAUGGUGAUAUUUACGCCAGUUUCUACAACUCUGGAUUGCUUGAUACCUUUAUAGGAGAAGGCAAAGAGUAUAUUUUUGUGUCUAACAUAGAUAAUCUGGGUGCCACAGUGGAUCUGUAUAUUCUUAAUCAUCUAAUGAACCCACCCAAUGGAAAACGCUGUGAAUUUGUCAUGGAAGUCACAAAUAAAACACGUGCAGAUGUAAAGGGCGGGACACUCACUCAAUAUGAAGGCAAACUGAGACUGGUGGAAAUUGCUCAAGUGCCAAAAGCACAUGUAGACGAGUUCAAGUCUGUAUCAAAGUUCAAAAUAUUUAAUACAAACAACCUAUGGAUUUCUCUUGCAGCAGUUAAAAGACUGCAGGAGCAAAAUGCCAUUGACAUGGAAAUCAUUGUGAAUGCAAAGACUUUGGAUGGAGGCCUGAAUGUCAUUCAAUUAGAAACUGCAGUAGGGGCUGCCAUCAAAAGUUUUGAGAAUUCUCUAGGUAUUAAUGUGCCAAGGAGCCGUUUUCUGCCUGUCAAAACCACAUCAGAUCUCUUGCUGGUGAUGUCAAACCUCUAUAGUCUUAAUGCAGGAUCUCUGACAAUGAGUGAAAAGCGGGAAUUUCCUACAGUGCCCUUGGUUAAAUUAGGCAGUUCUUUUACGAAGGUUCAAGAUUAUCUAAGAAGAUUUGAAAGUAUACCAGAUAUGCUUGAAUUGGAUCACCUCACAGUUUCAGGAGAUGUGACAUUUGGAAAAAAUGUUUCAUUAAAGGGAACGGUUAUCAUCAUUGCAAAUCAUGGUGACAGAAUUGAUAUCCCACCUGGAGCAGUAUUAGAGAACAAGAUUGUGUCUGGAAACCUUCGCAUCUUGGACCACUGAAAUGAAAAAUACUGUGGACACUUAAAUAAUGGGCUAGUUUCUUACAAUGAAAUGUUCUCUAGGAUUCUAAAAUAGGCAGGUACUUUACUAUGUUACUGUACCCUGCAGUGUUGAUUUUUAAAAUAGAGUUUUCUGCAGUAUGCUUUUAGUCUAAGAAAAGCACAGAUGGAGCAAUACUUUCCUUCUUUGAAGAGAAUCCCAAAAGUUAGUUCAUCUUAAAGUGCAAUAUUGUUUAAUCUUAAAACUGGGCAACUUUGGAAGAACUUUUAACAGAAGCCUCAAUGAUGAUCACUUUGAAUUGCUUGUGAUUUCAAAAAUAAAGCAGUGAAGCAA